AGUGUGCUUAGUGCUGAGCAGGGUUUCAGAGCUCACCCCCAGGAGGGUGCAGACCUCAGCCAAGGUCGCAGAGCAGAGGAGACCCGUGGGCUGGGAUUCCACCUGUGCCCACCCUGGCAGCAUCCCACCUCCUGAGUCCUCUCGGCACCCAGCAAGAGUCCCUUCAGUGACUUCGAGCGUGCAUUGAGAGCCCAGUAACACUGGGGGGCAACUGCCACAAAGACACAGCCUCAGCCAGGCGCAGUGACUCAUGCCUGUAAUCCCAGCACCUUGGGAGGCCAAGGCUUGUGGAUCACCUGAGGUCAGGAGUUUGAGACCAGCCGGACCAACAUGGAGAAACCCCAUCUCUACUAAAAAUACAAAAAAAUUAGCUAGGCAUUGUGGCGCAUGCCUGUAAUCCCGGCUACUCGGGAGGCUGAGGGAGGAGAAGCACUUGAACCCAGGAGGCGCGGUUGCAGUGAGCCGAGAUCGCCCCAUUGCACUCCAGCCUGGGCAACAAGAGCGAAACUCCAUCUCAAAAUAAUAAUAAUAACAAUAAUAGUAAGACUCAGCCUCCCCGCUCUGGGACACUCAGUCUGAUGGGGCAGGCUGGUCAGAAGACAUAGAGCCAUGGUGUGUUUGGAACUUUCACAGAGGGAAGCCUGGGGCUCGGGAAGCCCGGAAAAGAUGCCGGCGCAGCCUGAGGGCUUGUACAGGUUGAAGUUCAUGAGUUCGCCCAGCCUCAGUGACCUGGGCAAGAGAGAGCCGGCCGCCGCCGCGGACGAGCGGGGCACGCAGCAGCGCCGGGCCUGCGCCAACGCCACCUGGAACAGCAUCCACAACGGGGUGAUCGCCGUCUUCCAGCGCAAGGGGCUGCCCGACCAGGAGCUCUUCAGCCUCAACGAGGGCGUCCGGCAGCUGUUGAAGACAGAGCUGGGGUCCUUCUUCACGGAGUACCUGCAGAACCAGCUGCUGACAAAAGGCAUGGUGAUCCUUCGGGACAAGAUUCGCUUCUAUGAGGGACAGAAGCUGCUGGACUCACUGGCAGAGACCUGGGACUUCUUCUUCAGUGACGUGCUGCCCAUGCUGCAGGCCAUCUUCUACCCGGUGCAGGGCAAGGAGCCAUCGGUGCGCCAGCUGGCCCUGCUGCACUUCCGGAAUGCCAUCACCCUCAGUGUGAAGCUAGAGGAUGCGCUGGCCCGGGCCCAUGCCCGUGUGCCCCCUGCCAUCGUGCAGAUGCUGCUGGUGCUGCAGGGGGUACAUGAGUCCAGGGGCGUGACUGAGGACUACCUGCGCCUGGAGACGCUGGUCCAGAAGGUGGUGUCGCCAUACCUGGGCACCUACGGCCUCCACUCCAGCGAGGGGCCCUUCACCCAUUCCUGCAUCCUGGAAAAGCGCCUCCUCCGCCGCUCCCGCUCGGGGGACGUGCUGGCCAAGAACCCUGUGGUGCGCUCCAAGAGCUACAACACGCCUCUGCUGAACCCCGUGCAGGAGCACGAGGCGGAGGGCGCGGCGGCCGGCGGUACCAGCAUCCGCAGGCACUCUGUGUCGGAGAUGACGUCCUGCCCCGAGCCUCAGGGCUUCUCCGACCCGCCCGGCCAGGGCCCCACCGGGACCUUCAGGUCCUCCCCGGCGCCCCACUCAGGGCCCUGCCCCAGCAGACUGUACCCCACGACCCAGCCCCCUGAGCAGGGCUUGGAUCCCACCCGCAGCUCCCUGCCCCGCUCCAGCCCGGAGAACCUGGUGGACCAGAUCCUGGAGUCCGUGGACUCGGAUUCUGAAGGGAUUUUCAUUGACUUUGGCCGGGGCCGGGGCUCUGGCAUGUCCGACUUGGAGGGCUCUGGGGGCCGGCAGAGUGUCGUGUGAGGCCUCACAGCUGGCCUUGAGUUUUUACUGACACGUCCCUGUGUGCGGGGGUGUCCAUGUGGCGUGUGUGUGAGUGAGACUUUUUUACUGCGUCCCGUCCCGCCAGCCCUAUCGGCCUCGUCACUGGCCUUGGUCACUUUGUAUUUCUGUCUUGGUUGGAAAUACCAUCAGCCUUCCUUGCUCGGCCCAGGUCUGUUUCAGGCAUCUGAGUCGGCGUUUACCCAGGGGCCGGGCCAGAGACGGGGGUCGGCCGCUCGCUCCCACGCUCCUCCUGCCCCAGCCCUCUGGUGUCCACACCUGCCCACAGAGAAUGUAAACCCAGUGGGCUCUGCCCACGCCGGGCCCCAAAGUGACCAGACUCCAGCACACCUGUCUCCUCCUGCCUGGGGUGGCCAUGGGGAUGGAAGGGGGUGGAAUAAAACCUGUCAACCUGG